GGAGGGACGCAAGCGGGAGCGCGGAGCCCGGCGACUAGCUCCCUCGCGUGCCGCAGCGGCGACCCUUUCUACUUGGUCUUUCCUUUUCCUCCGAGCGCCGGGAGGAGGAAGCUCCCGCUAGCGUCUCCCACUUCCCGCGGCUGGAGGAAGGGGCCACGCUGAGGGAACAAGACAGGGAGCAGAGGCGGCGGGGUUCAGGCGAGCGGGAAGCGGGAAGCGAGAGGCGGGUGUGAGAUGGGGUCCUGAGGCUGGAAGGGAGCCCGGGGACAACUGGAGUUGCACACGCUCGGAAGGCGGGAGGCGGCAAGGAGAAGGCUGCCUUAGAGGCUGGGACCCGGGCUGUCCGCCAGGGCUGGGAGACACUGGAGGAGGCCGGCCGAUGAUUACGCGCGAUGCCAACGACGACUGCCCUACGGUGGACCGCGGCUGCCCGUGUGCGGAGGAAAGGGAGAGGCGGCUGGGUGCCGGCUGCGCUGCGGUCCGUGAGCCAGGACAGAGUCCCAGGCUGUACAGUGAUGGGCGGAGAGACUCGCAGUCCUGAGAAGUAUUAUGGGCUGUACUGGGAGAUUUGGAGAGGGUGGAGGAGGGGCGGUCUGAGGGAUUCCGGGCGGCACCGCUAAGGCGAUGCCGCGAGCAGCAUCCGCGCCCUCUCCUUCCCGCCCCAGCCCGGGUUUGUUCAGUCAGGGCUCCAGCCCGGCGGCCGGGAGGAAGAAAAGGAAGAGGGAAGGAGCCUUUACCUGGCUCUGACGCGACGGGUCCCAGGCCCCCGGCUCCGCUUCCCACUCAGAGCUCUCCUCCCCUCUCUUCCCCGCCACCCGUUUCUACGCAGAUCUGUGCCCCAGUCCCUGGAGGAGCCUCCGCCAACUCCGCAGGACCCCGCCGGGAAGUAGAGCCCACCCCUUUACCAAUCACCGCCCGUUUUCUAUCGACCGAUGGGGCCCAUAGCCAAUAGGAAGAGCUGAUCCCGAGAGGCCCGGAAUGAGGGGGAGGAGCUGGCAAAACUUGGAGGUGUGACUAGCACUGCCGAGGCGUGGUCACAGAUUAAGCUCCACCCCGGGUUGUUGAACCCCUAAGUAGAACUGAUGGGCGGGAUUAAGGUGGAACCGACGACCAAACACAAACUCUUGAGCUGAGGCACGGCCAAUUGGGCCGGGGUAGAGAGGAGGGGUGUUGCGGGGAAUUUUAACCAAUAAAGAGUAGAGACCGGUGGAGACUGUAGACCCUCUUCCAAUAAGAAGCGGGAAGGGCGUGCCUUGCCACUUUCACUAGGGCUAAAGCAGGGUUUGCCGAAACCUCCCGAAGCCGGCCAAUGAGAUCGGAGGCGGAGCCAAGCUCAGCCGACCAGAAAGCCGAAUUGAUCUCAGCACCGUUACUGGGGCGGUGCCUACGGUCUUCAAGCCACUAAGCUCUCGUGAGGGGAGGCCCCGGAGCCUUCCAAUGAGGGACUGGGGCUAACUCUAGUUCUUCCAAUCGGUGCGCGGCGCUGGCAAUUCAAACUGAUACCGGGUUGGAGAGGCAGGAAAAGCGGAAGAGGGAGCGAAAACCAACGUGUUCGGUGACAGACCCCAGCGCCGACUGAGCCUCUAAAGCGACUUCAGCUCUGCCCCACCAACACCACCGCGCGCCCGGGAACAGCCGCUCCGGGAAGAAACCUGAGGGGACUGCGGGGGGCACGAGGGACAGCUGAGGGAAGGGAGGACGCGAGAGAAACAGCGCGAGCACGCUGAGGGCCGGGGGUUGCCAGGAGAGGGGCCCGCGGACCCGCAGAGCGGAGGAAGGUCCGGGAGAAAAGGGGCGGGACGGAGGAGAAUCCGGGAUCGCCUGGCAGAAAAAGAGAAGGGAGUUUCUGAAUCCUGGGAAGAGGAGGCGUGGGUAGGGACGCUUAGCCCGAGAUCCGACAGCAGGGAACCGGAGCGCUCCGGGGGAGGGGCUUAAUGCUGGGGAAGGGAUGUCUUAAAAGAGGAGAAGCUUUAAAUUAGACGAUCGGAGAAGGCUGAGGGAAUUGCUAUGAAGGGGCGGGAGCUGAAGUGUAGAGGACUCCUUUAGACAGCAGAAAGGGAAAGCCGUUGAGAAGUUCCCUUCAAACUCCACCUGCCUCCUCUCCAAUUCAAACUCCACUCCCUUCUCCAAAAGUUAAAAGGAAAGCCAAGUUUACCACGCUCCCCUGUUCCUACUCAAUAAAUACUUCUUCUACUCCGCCACCGGGAAAACAGAAAAAAAAACUAAUUUCCUUCCCAAUAUUAGGACUUAGAAAAGCUCUAGGUCCCGCAAUUUGAAUUUUAGCCUAGGGGAAUCAAAAUAGUAGGAGCAUUACUCUUGUUUCCUUUUUCAAAAUCCCACACCUCAUCCUUCCUGCGACGCCAUGUCCACCAACAUUUGUAGUUUCAAGGACAGGUGCGUGUCCAUCCUGUGUUGCAAAUUCUGUAAACAAGUGCUCAGCUCUAGGGGAAUGAAGGCUGUUUUGCUGGCUGAUACUGAAAUAGACCUUUUCUCUACAGACAUCCCUCCUACCAACGCAGUGGACUUCACUGGAAGAUGCUAUUUCACCAAAAUCUGCAAAUGUAAACUGAAGGACAUCGCAUGUUUAAAAUGUGGGAACAUUGUAGGUUAUCAUGUGAUUGUUCCAUGUAGUUCCUGUCUUCUUUCCUGCAACAACAGACACUUCUGGAUGUUUCACAGCCAGGCAGUUUAUGAUAUUAACAGACUAGACUCCACAGGUGUAAACGUCCUACUUCGGGGCAACUUGCCAGAGAUAGAAGAGAGUACAGAUGAAGAUGUGUUAAAUAUCUCAGCAGAGGAGUGUAUUAGAUAAAUGGAAUUAUGAUAUAUAUGAUAUACAAACUUUUUUCUAUUUAAAAAUAUAUUAAUGGAUCAACUUUAAAAUUGUUAGUUGCCAGUGAUCUUUUUUGGAAAACAAAAAUGGGGCAUUUGUUGAUUUAUUUAUUUUCUGUCUCUAAUUAGUUACCUCAGUUUGAUUGAAGCCAGUGGAGUUGUGCUUUUCCUCUACUUCUACUUCCUCUCCCCCACCUUUUUCUGCCCAGUGUAGGUGUAUUCUUAAAUUCAGACGGGAAGAUUCUUUCACAUAUCACUCAGUUACCUCCCAAUCUGGGGGAGUUUUUCUUACAACUUGAUACCAGAUACCAUUAAUUUUACAUUCCUGAAUAAAGGCCUAGUACCCACGCAUAUUUCAACCAUGCAUAUAUCAAGUUCAACCGAGUUUUAAUAGGGGAUUAAAAAAACAAGCUGUUAGGUUUCCAUGGGCACUGGUUCUCAUAGGUUCUAUUGGUGAUAACUGCUUUAACAUGGAGCAAGAGUUUGUGAAUCAGGAAAUAGAAUAAAUUAAAAUUUAAAAUAUAUAGAGGAAUCCUCUUGAUUGCUCAGCAUGAUGUUAGAUAAAUGAGUUUGUCAGAAAAUAUCAGUAUACGCUGUUUACCAAUGUUAUUUAUUUACAUUCUUCUAAAGCCAUUAUGGAUAUUGUAUUAUGAGAGCUAAACCUAAAUAAGUUAUCCUGUUCCCUAGGACCUUCUCUGUAAAUAGUGAAUUUUAGACGAGUGGUCUGUCCUAAAUCUUAAAUAGAAAAAAAAACUAAAGCGAUUUGCUUAAGCCAUUGUACAUUAUAAAGAGCUGUUUUGUUUUGCUUUGCUUUGCUUUGUUUUGUUUUUUUAAAGCUGCAUUCAGAGCUACAAAGGAAUAGGAAAGUAGGGUAGUGUUGGAUUCUGGUUUUAUGUAACUCUAAAAUAAAUGUAUCUCUUUAAUAUCUCAGUUGUAGGGAUUUUGUCAAUACCAAAGCAGACUGAGUUGUGGUUUUGUAAAUAAAGUUUUUUCUAAAAAUGACCAUUCUUCCUUUAAUUUUUUGUUAUGCCCACAUAUUGUAUGUAAAAAUAUAAAUAAAUAGUACUUAAAGUAUAGAA